UAUACCUCAGUAUAAUUGGCUUUUGUUAUAAUUCUAUACAUUUUAUUUUAUGUAUUUGGAAAAGAGGUCAUAGGACUGAUUAUCAAAGGGCCCAUGUCACAAAGAAUGUUUAAGAACCCCCUGUUCUGGAAUAUUGUCAUCACCUCUGUGGUCUAAGCUAGGCUGCUGCCCCCUCUCAUUUACACAAGUAGGAAGAGGAAAGAGAACCUGGAGGAGGUAUGGCACACAUGGCCUCUGCUUACAUAUCAGAGAACUCAGUGUCCUGGCCACAGUCAAAUACAAUAGAGGCCAGGAAAGGUUGUGUAUCUCGGCUAACACAUGUCCAGCUACAAGUUUCUAUUACAGCUGAUGAAAGAGACAACUAGCGGGCUCUGUACAUUGAUUCAAUCCUGUCUGAGGAUGACCAUAUAGAAGCAUAAGGAGAGGAGACAAGUGAGUCAGAUAGUGGCCAAGUUUCUGAUUUGGGAUACCAUUCACAAAGAUGGGGAGAAGAAAAAGUAGAAGACAUUUGGAAGAAGAAAAAACAUUGCAAUUGGACAAGUUGACUUUGAGAUUCCUAUGAGCAGGGGUAUACUGACAAACCUGCUCUCCCAGAAAACAAAAACAAAAAUCCUGUUUAUAGCCUUUGAUGACUUCCACGAUCUAAAUGUACCCAUCAUGGCCUAUUUCAAGCUACCAAGAUGAUGUCACUGAAUGAGCAGUUGGAAAGAAAUGUGCAUGAAUAGGCUUUCAUAAGCCAGCAAAGGCUGGGUUCAGCUCACCUCUACCAGUGAGGAUUUCCAAAUGGAGGCAUCUUAAAGACACUGGGAUAUGCAGAGCUCAAGCUAAGGAGUAGAAUCUAGUGCAUUCUGUGCUACCUGACACCUAUUGGUAUCUAAAUUGCUCUGCGCAUCCAGAUUCAAAACACAGAACUUUUUGGAUUCCACAAAACGAAACCACUCACACAAAACCUUUCACACAAUUGAGACUUCACUGAGGAUUUGGGUCCUGGAAGGAGGAAGCAACAAUCCUGAGUGAAACCUCGACAAGAAGUAUCCAAUAGGACAUUCGUCAUGUCCUCAAAUACAAUGCUUCAAAAAACGCUGCUGAUCUUGAUCUCUUUUUCAGUAGUAACCUGGAUGAUUUUUAUAAUUUCUCAGAACUUCACAAAGCUUUGGUCUGCUCUAAACUUAUCCAUCUCUGUCCAUUACUGGAACAACUCCGCAAAGUCCUUAUUCCCUAAAACAUCACUGAUACCAUUAAAGCCACUAACAGAGACUGAACUCAGAAUAAAGGAAAUCAUAGAGAAACUAGAUCAGCAGAUCCCACCCAGACCUUUCACCCAUGUGAACACCACCACCAGUGCCACACACAGCACAGCCACCAUCCUCAACCCUCGAGAUACAUACUGCAGGGGAGACCAGCUGGACAUCCUACUGGAGGUGAGGGACCACUUGGGACAGAGGAAGCAAUAUGGUGGGGAUUUCCUGAGGGCCAGGAUGUCCUCCCCAGCACUGACGGCAGGUGCUUCAGGAAAGGUGAUGGACUUCAACAAUGGCACCUACCUGGUCAGCUUCACUCUGUUCUGGGAGGGCCAGGUCUCCCUGUCUCUGCUGCUCAUCCACCCCAGUGAAGGGGCGUCGGCUCUCUGGAGGGCAAGGAACCAAGGCUAUGAUAAAAUUAUUUUCAAAGGCAAAUUUGUUAAUGGCACCUCUCAUGUCUUCACUGAAUGUGGCCUGACCCUAAACUCAAAUGCUGAACUCUGUGAAUAUCUGGAUGACAGAGACCAAGAAGCCUUCUAUUGUAUGAAGCCUCAACACAUGCCCUGUGAGGCUCUGACCUACAUGACCACCCGGAAUAGAGAGGUAUCUUAUCUUACAGACAAGGAAAACAGCCUUUUCCACAGGUCCAAAGUGGGAGUUGAAAUGAUGAAGGAUCGUAAACACAUUGAUGUCACUAAUUGUAACAAGAGAGAAAAAAUAGAAGAGACAUGCCAAGUUGGAAUGAAGCCUCCUGUCCCUGGUGGUUAUACUUUACAAGGAAAAUGGAUAACAACAUUUUGCAACCAGGUUCAGUUAGACACAAUUAAGAUAAAUGGCUGUUUGAAAGGCAAACUCAUUUACCUCCUGGGAGACUCUACACUACGUCAGUGGAUCUACUACUUCCCCAAAGUUGUAAAAACACUGAAGUUUUUUGAUCUUCAUGAAACUGGAAUCUUUAAGAAACAUUUGCUUCUGGAUGCAGAAAGACACACUCAGAUUCAAUGGAAAAAACAUAGCUAUCCCUUCGUCACUUUCCAGCUCUACUCUCUGAUAGAUCAUGAUUAUAUCCCUCGGGAAAUUGACCGGCUAUCAGGUGACAAAAACACAGCCAUCGUCAUCACCUUUGGCCAGCACUUUAGACCAUUUCCCAUUGACAUUUUUAUUCGCAGGGCCAUCGGUGUUCAAAAGGCUAUUGAAAGACUGUUCCUAAGAAGCCCAGCCACUAAAGUGAUUAUUAAGACAGAAAACAUCAGGGAGAUGCACAUAGAGACAGAGAGGUUUGGAGACUUCCAUGGUUAUAUUCACUAUCUUAUCAUGAAGGAUAUUUUCAAAGACCUCAACGUGGGCAUCAUUGAUGCCUGGGACAUGACCAUUGCAUAUGGCACUGACACUAUCCACCCACCUGAUCAUGUGAUUGGAAAUCAGAUUAACAUGUUCUUAAACUACAUUUGCUAAGGGAUAAAUACUAUACAAAAUCACUAGGAACCAAUCUCUGCACAUAAUCCCACAUGUAUUGUAAAGUAAGUUUUACUCAUUUUAGGAACUAAGGAAAAUAAAUUUAAAAGAAUCUGUUUGGGGAGGAAGGCUAUGUAAGGACAAUGACAACUGAUAAGGGAUGCAAAACCAAGAGAAUCAUUCAUGAAGAAUGACUAUACCAUGCCUGGUUCUGAUGCUCGUUUAAAAUAUUAAAAAAGUUUUUUAAAAGCCAUGUUAUUAAGCUGAUUUGAAAAUAUCUGUACAAAUUCAUGAUGCUUUCUAUUUCCAAUAUAGAUAUUUCCUAGCUCUGUCUAUUGAAAAGGCCUAGGAGCAAUGAUAACCCAUUAGCAAUAAUCACUCCGAGCACCCUAACUGUGAUGUCUAAGAACCCUUCCUCAAUAAAAGAAAAGAGGCAUCCUUGAAGGGAAGGCUGAUUCCAGGACUGGAACAGAAAAUAUGUAUACCAUGAGCCUGGACAUCUUGUUAUGCCAGAAAGCAAAUAAUCAAAGACAAAUGGAAUCAUAUCAUGGAACAGAGGAGGUAACCCAAAGGAGUCUCUUCAUUGGCCAUAGAUAGAUUAGUUUUAGCAUCAAAAAGACUAAUGACUGCAGUUAAUUGAAAUACAUAAUAUAUAAAAUCCAUGAGGUCAUAGCAAUACAAAAAGAGACAUGCAAGAAUAAAAGCAAAAUCUCUCAUGUGUCGUAAGUGGAGUUGGGUAAACCCUUAUUUUGAAAAUUGGCAACAAAAGGGAAAUAUAUGAACAUUUAUCCUCUUUCCUGUUAAAGAGAAAAUCAAUAACCCUAAUAGAUAAAGGAAAUUUCUUCUUUUUGGAAGAAUUACAGCUAAUGAAUACAGAAAGAACGACAGAAUUAGGAAAGCACCAUUUAAAAACUUCUACUCAAAUAAGUAAAUAAGGCAGAGAUCAUCAGUGAAUGAACUUUUUUAAAAGGUUUGAUUGGAACUUUACUAUGGAUAUAGCAGGCUGUCACUUCUGAAUCCACUGCUCAAACUUAGCUUUAUUAAUUUUAAAGCUUUGUAACAGCAGGACAACUGGUCAUUAUGUCCUACAUGAUUUGAUGCAAUGUAAAGUAUACAACACCACCUAUGAAGGAGCGAGAUCUGUAAGAAAGAUGCUCAAUUUGGAAGUCAUCAUUAUAUAUAGGUGCCUGCUAAAAAUGAGGAGAUGGUAAUAUUUUCACACACAAAGGGAACUCUCAUACACUCUUGGUGGGAAUGUAAGUUGGUACAGCCAUUAUGGAAAACAGUAUGGCAGUUCCCCUAAAAACAGAACUACCAUAUGACCCAGCAAUCCCUCUGCUGAGUAUCCCAAAGGAAAUGAAAUCAGCACUUCAUAGAGAUAUCUGCAUUCUCAUGCUCACUGCAGCAUUAUUCACAAUAGCCAAGACAGAGAAACAACAUAAGUGCCCAUCAAUAGAUGAACAGAUAAAUAAUUUGCAGUAUAUAUGUACAAUGGAAUAUCAUUCAGCCUUACAAAAGGAGAUGCUGCUAUAUUUGCAAUAACAUGGGUGAACCUGGAGGACGUUACGCUAAGUAAAAUAACAAUAUUGAAGGAAAGAAAUAAUACUGAAAGAAAAAUAUUGCUUGAUCUCACUUAUAUAUGGAACUUAAAAACUACACAUAGAAACAGGGUAGAAUGGUAGUUAUCCAGGCUGGGAGGAAGAGAAAACAGGGAGGUGUAGGUCAAAGGGUACAAACUUGCAGUUCUAUUGGAUGAAUGUCUAGAGAGCUAAUGUACAGCAUGAGAACUAUAGUUAAUAUUGUAUAUGGAAAAUUUGCUGAGAGACUAGAUUUUAGGUAUUCUACCUCAAUUAAAAAGGUAAUUGUGGCCAGGCACGGUGGCUUACGCCUGUAAUGCCAGCACUUUGGGAGGCCUAAGCGGGAGGAUCACGAGGUCAGGAGAUCGAGACCACAGUGAAACCCCGUCUUUACUAAAAAUACAAAAAAAAAUUAGCGGGCAAGCUCGCCGAGAUGGCACCACUGCACUCCAGACUGGGCUACAGAGCGAGACUCUGUCUCAAAAAACAAACAAACAAACAAAAGGUAAUUGUGCAGUGAGGAAUAUGUUAAUAUACUGACUACAGUAAUCAUUUCACUAUGCAUAUGUAUAUCAAAACAUCACACUGUAUACCUUAAAUGUAUGCAAUAAAAAAUAAAAGAUACAUACACAAAAUUCUUUAAAUGUCCCACACACAAGACAAAUACGUGUUCAAAUACAUCAGUCUCUGAAGCCUCUGCACCACUCUACACGCUGCUCCUUCUGACUAGAAUGCCCUCCUGCCCCUCCUUCCACCUGUCAAACUCCCAAUCACCCUUUAAAACCAGAUUGAAUUAUUUUCUUCUGUGAAGCUUUCCCUGACACCCCGGGAAAGAAUAAUGUUUCCACAGUGUUUUGUCAUUUACUCCAUAAAAGAAACAAAAACAUGUAUUUUUAAAAGUAUCUGUUAUCUCUAAUAGCUUGUAAACAUCUUGAGGAAAGAGACUAAGUUUUGCUUCUUUUUCCCCCAAAGAGAACUUUAUUAAAACAUUUACCAUCUCUUUAGAGAGAGGUUUUACCAUCUCUUUAGAAAGCUCCAGAAUCUACAACCAGGAAUAAGUGUUAAUGGGAUAGAACCAAUGAGAGAACAGCAUAUGAUAGUGAAAUGUACUUUAUUAUUAAUACGAAUUCAGUGGGCUCACAGAAUGAACCUUUUUGCCAAACGGGGGGAAAGCAUUUUCUGUAAAGUAUCUUUAGAAAAAUAUGUAUAAUUUGAAAAAUGGUUAUCCAAAUUUAACAUUUGUCAUAUAAAAGGCUCAUAAAACGUGUGUGGCUGUGUUUCUCAAAAUUGUGGGGUCAAUUGGUCACAUUAUGCCUAGACAUUCUGGUUUUGUUCUUGGGGUUAAUAAUGGUUGUGGUCUUAUAAGAAAAGGAAAUCUGGAAAUCUUGUCCCUGUUAUUAAUACACCUGUCAUUACUAAUAAAAGUGGUUUGUUGAUAUGCUAAAUAGGUUGAAAAA